GUAAUUGCCUCGGUGAUGUCGUGGGUUCAAGCAGCCUCCUUGAUCCAGGGCCCUGGAGACAAAGGGGACGUGUUUGACGAAGAAGCAGACGAGUCGCUCCUGGCGCAGCGGGAAUGGCAGAGUAACAUGCAAAGACGAGUCAAAGAAGGUUAUAGAGAUGGAAUAGAUGCUGGCAAAGCAGUUACUCUUCAACAGGGCUUCAAUCAAGGUUAUAAGAAAGGUGCAGAAGUCAUUUUAAACUAUGGACGACUCCGAGGAACAUUGAGGAACUCAACGGAUUGGAGCCUACUGGGCUUGAGAGCCCCGCUGAGGAGUCCGGAGGUUGGGACGCAACUACUGCCGCGUCCCCUCCCGGUCCCCGGCCACAUGGCGAGCGGGGCGACACCGAAGCAGCCCACGGAGCUCGAGGCGACGCUGCUGAGCCUGGUUCCCCAAAGCGGCCGCGCCACUCCCCGCUUCCCCGCCCGGCUCCGGGCCCCAGGCCCUGGGACGCCGAGCCACCGCCGGCGUUUCAGACGCAAACCCCACCGCGACCCUGCAGCAGCCUGCCCCGCCUGGCCGCCAGAGGCACCUUCCAACUCCGAAACACAUUUUUCAACAUAUAAUAGAAUCAUUAUCAGAGGUGGACACAUUUAGAAGUUGUUCUUAAUCAGAGGGCAGCUUGUGCUUAGGAAAGCCAGCCUCAGUCCUCAGCACCCAGCACCCAGUGCUGCAGGUUUCUCCUGGGUGAAGAUGGACCAGCCCACCUUGGCCCUCCGGCAAGCUAGAACAAUAUGUACACGUCUCUCAAACUAUGAAGAGAAGAUUUGGGAGGAGUAUGAGAAAAUCCUCAAUACCAAACUAGCAGAGCAAUACGAGUCGUUUGUGAAAUUCACACAUGAGCAGAUUAUGCGACCAUGUGGGACAAGCCCAACAAACUAUGUGUCUUGAAGCUUUUUGUUGCAGAUCUCGGUACCAGGUUUGACCUCAAGGCAUGGUUGCUAUACAUUUUUUGCAACUGUUUGAUAUCACAUUUCAGCUCCAACUUUGCAUCCUGAGAACAUUCCAACGUUUCUGCAGGUCCAUUUUAUACGACUUGAAAGACCUUAAAACUUUCUGGUUGCCACAGGUAUAUCUUUCUUUUCUGUUCAUCCAGUAAAUAGUCAUACCCUACUGUGACAGAUUUUUCCAAACAAAAAUACCUGGAGCAGCAGUGUAGCAAAAUAUGCCUUCAGUGGCACUCAACAAAUGGAGUUUCCCCAAGCACAGUUCUGUAAGAAGUGUGUGUGAGAGUGUGUAUGUGUCUGUACAUGUACUUUAGAUUAUGGUUUGUAUUGUGCAAAUUUUUUUGAUCUUGGGGAUUCUGGCUGUGGAUUUGAUGCAGAAAAUUAUGGUUAAAAACUAUGGUCUACAGAAGAUACUUAAUGCUUUGUGACUAUAUAAAUUGUAACAGUGGAUUGUUUUAUGUGUAGGUAUUAUUGUUAAAUAUGGGGACUGUUCACCAGGCACAAAAUAGGAAUCAUAAAUUAGGAUGCAGGCUGGGUAUGGUGGCUCAUGCCUGUAAUCCCAGCACUUUGGGAGGAGGCCGAGCUGGGCGGAUCGCUUGAGGAGAGUUCGUGAUCAGCCUGGCCAACGUGGAGAAACCCUGUCCCUACUAAAAAUACAAAAAUUAGGUGGACAUGGUGGCGAGCACCUGUAAUCCCAGCUUCUCGGGAGGCUGAGGCAGGAGAAUCACUUGAACCAGGGAGGCAGAGGUUGCAGUGAGCCCAGAUUGUGCCACUGCACUCUAGCCUCGGUGACAGAGUAAGAUUCCAUCUCAAAGAAAAAAAAAAAAAGUGAAGAUGGCCAUUGGCUGUGGUUAUGACAAUACAGUGAAAGUCUGUUGUCUUAGAUAUACAAAUACAUAGUGAGAAAUUAGAACAAACUGGAGACUGGCCUUUGACACAUGGACUCUGCCUAGCUGUGUUAGAAAAAUAUUUAACUCCAAGCCUUAAAAUUCCCAAAUGGAGUUGGUGCUUACCUCAUUCACACAAUCCAAGAGUUCACUGGGUCCUGAACCUCUAAAGGGAAAAGGUCUCCCCUGGAGCAGGAGCAUCAGAGUUUGCUCGGGGGCAUAAGGUAGGUGAGUGCUGGGCCGAGGCAGGCUCCCCUGGCACUGCUAGUUGCAGGAGCACUUUACCUUUGUAUCAGUUACUAAAAACAAAAUUUGAAUCCUUUGGUCAGGUUCCCCCAAAUUAUUUUGAGGUAGCCAUGUUUAAGUGCUUGAGCUUUUGUGUUGGCAAACCCCUGCCCAAGGUUGCUAAUAGGGUAUUCUGCCCCUUGUUUCCACAGCUGAGGCACAGAAAGUAGCCUCUUUUGUGAGGAGUUGGGAGUUAAGUAUACAUUUAUUUUUUUACCAUGAUUUGUUCAGGACCACAUUUUACAAGAUACCUUGUUUCCUUUAUUAUUGUUUCUGGAAAGUCCUAUUCAUAUUAUUUUAUUUGAAUAUAGAAUAUAGUUUUUUUAAAUGAGGGCUUAUUUUGAAAAAUUCUGAGCUUAAUUCAAAUUUAUGCCAAUACCUUCCCAAAUAAGGUAAUAGUCAAAGACAGAUGUUCUGAUCAAAUGGCUUAGAGAUAGUCCUGGAAUAUUCAUAUUCAAAGAUUCCUUAUUAAUGAAUGUCUUUAACUUAAAUCUACCCAAUAAUUGCAACAUGGUUCUUUGUACAUUUUCAUUAUAUGGUGUUAACAAGCUUCACUGCAAACAAAUAAAUUACUUAAGUUA